AGAGGGGACUGAGCAUGGAUUUCGGACUGGCCCUCCUGCUGGCGGGGCUUCUGGGGCUCCUCCUCGGCCAGUCCCUCCAGGUGAAGCCCCUGCAGGUGGAGCCCCCGGAGCCGGUGGUGGCCGUGGCCUUGGGCGCCUCGCGCCAGCUCACCUGCCGCCUGGCCUGCGCGGACCGCGGGGCCUCGGUGCAGUGGCGGGGCCUGGACACCAGCCUGGGCGCGGUGCAGUCGGACACGGGCCGCAGCGUCCUCACCGUGCGCAACGCCUCGCUGUCGGCGGCCGGGACCCGCGUGUGCGUGGGCUCCUGCGGGGGCCGCACCUUCCAGCACACCGUGCAGCUCCUUGUGUACGCCUUCCCGGACCAGCUGACCGUCUCCCCAGCAGCCCUGGUGCCUGGUGACCCGGAGGUGGCCUGUACGGCCCACAAAGUCACGCCCGUGGACCCCAACGCGCUCUCCUUCUCCCUGCUCGUCGGGGGCCAGGAACUGGAGGGGGCGCAAGCCCUGGGCCCGGAGGUGCAGGAGGAGGAGGAGGAGCCCCAGGGGGACGAGGACGUGCUGUUCAGGGUGACAGAGCGCUGGCGGCUGCCGCCCCUGGGGACCCCUGUCCCGCCCGCCCUCUACUGCCAGGCCACGAUGAGGCUGCCUGGCUUGGAGCUCAGCCACCGCCAGGCCAUCCCCGUCCUGCACAGCCCGACCUCCCCGGAGCCUCCCGACACCACCUCCCCGGAGUCUCCCGACACCACCUCCCCGGAGUCUCCCGACACCACCUCCCAGGAGCCUCCCGACACCACCUCCCCGGAGCCUCCCGACAAGACCUCCCCGGAGCCCGCCCCCCAGCAGGGCUCCACACACACCCCCAGGAGCCCAGGCUCCACCAGGACUCGCCGCCCUGAGAUCUCCCAGGCUGGGCCCACGCAGGGAGAAGUGAUCCCAACAGGCUCGUCCAAACCUGCGGGUGACCAGCUGCCCGCGGCUCUGUGGACCAGCAGUGCGGUGCUGGGACUGCUGCUCCUGGCCUUGCCCACCUAUCACCUCUGGAAACGCUGCCGGCACCUGGCUGAGGACGACACCCACCCACCAGCUUCUCUGAGGCUUCUGCCCCAGGUGUCGGCCUGGGCUGGGUUAAGGGGGACCGGCCAGGUCGGGAUCAGCCCCUCCUGAGUGGCCAGCCUUUCCCCCUGUGAAAGCAAAAUAGCUUGGACCCCUUCAAGUUGAGAACUGGUCAGGGCAAACCUGCCUCCCAUUCUACUCAAAGUCAUCCCUCUGUUCACAGAGAUGGAUGCAUGUUCUGAUUGCCUCUUUGGAGAAGCUCAUCAGAAACUCAAAAGAAGGCCACUGUUUGUCUCACCUACCCAUGACCUGAAGCCCCUCCCUGAGUGGUCCCCACCUUUCUGGACGGAACCACGUACUUUUUACAUACAUUGAUUCAUGUCUCACGUCUCCCUAAAAAUGCGUAAGACCAAGCUGUGCCCUGACCACCCUGGGCCCCUGUCGUCAGGACCUCCUGAGGCUUUGGCAAAUAAACCUCCUAAAAUGAUA